CUGCUAGUAGAGAUGGCUGAUUUUCUGGGGUAUGAGUCUUUGACAGCCACCUUAGGGUGUUGUUGGGAUGUUGGCAUGUCAGAAUUAUAGAGGGGGAGAGAUUUAAACUUAGUCUCUAAUGCCAGUUACAUGUUUACUCCUUUCUUUUCUCCAGUAAUCCCAAAGUUCUAUUAAGGCAGUGGUUUAUUAGCAUGGGCCCAGGAGCCUGACUGCGUUGGUUCAAAUCCCAGCUCUGCCACUUAAGUAAAAGCUUUGUGACCUUGGGCAGGUUACUUAACGUUUCAGUUCCUCAUUUUCCUCGCCUGUCAAAUGGUAAUGAUAGUGCCUACCACAUGGGAGACUGAAUGAGUUAAUACUUACAAAGCAAAUAGAACACAGCAUGUGUUGUUAUUAUAAUUUUAGUAUUAUCAUUUUUAGCAUUCAUUCUCAAUUGACCUGUUUUGUUUACUCUAUUCCCCAACAAGUAUGUACAUUUAAGAAUAGGCAUAAAAGUGGCCAGGCGCGGUGGCUCACACCUGUAAUCCCAGCACUUUGGGAGGCCGAGACUGGUGGAUCACGAGGUCAGGAGAUUGAGACCAUCCUGGCUAACAUGGUGAAACCCCGUCUCUACUAAAAAUACAAAAAAAAUUAGCCAGGUGUGGUGGCAGGAGCCUGUCAUCCCAGCUACCCGGGAGGCUGAGGCAGGAGAAUGGCGUGAACCCGGGGGGCGGAGCUUGCAGUGAGUCGAGAUUGCGCCACUGCACUCCAGCCUGGGCGACAGAGCAAGACUCUGUCUCAAAAAAAAAAAAGGCAUAAAAGUAAAAGAAUCAAGGACAUAGAGUUUAACAUUAGAACUGAAGUGAGUAAAAAGACUGGACGCACAUUUGGUCCAAGAGGCAUUGCUUUAUUGCUCUGGUUAAGGCUCAGACUUGGUAGUAGGCUUAGAAAAGAACUGAAGACAAGAAAAAGGGAGGGAGGAGGGCGCAGUGUGUUGCAUGGUUUGUCCUUGUUGAGGAGGAAAGCAAAUGCUAGGACUACAUUCUCAGGAAAAACCAAACUUGUGCUAGCACCUCAGAGGAAUUCUGUGUGGGGCCUGCCUCUGCUUUGACCUGGCAGUUGCAGGACACUUAGCCAGCUGCUGCCCUCUCCCAUCCCCCACUUUUGACUUCUCACAUACCCUUUUAUGUUGUCACUGCUGCCUCAGAGCAACACCCAACUCUAGAAUAAGGAUUCUUAAUAUGGAGCCCGAGAACCCUAGGAGGAAUCUAUGAAAUGAGCGUGAGAAGGUCUCUAUUAAUACCUGAAAUUACAGGCAAAAGUUUGUGUACAUGUUAGCAGGUAUCUUUUGUGGCAAGAGAGUCCAUGGCUUUUAUGAGAUUCUCAAAGGGCUGACAGACAUAAAAAUGUUAACCAUUGCUAUAGGAGACAGUUUAAACUCAGUAAUAACAGCUGCCAUUUAUUGAGUAUUUACGAGUGAGGCACUGAGUUAAGCUUUUACAUGAACAUCUUUUUAGUCCUCACAGCAACCCUGUGAGGUUAGUACUGUUGUUAGUACUGUUAGCACUGAGGUUAGUACUAUUCCUAUUUUACAGAUGAGGACACUGAAGUUGGGUAUCUUUCCAAGAUCACAGAGCUAGUAAAACAAGGAUUUAAGUGUAGGGCUGUUUUCUACAUUCAGCAUUUCAGCUCUCAGCCCCAACAAUGUUCUGCCUCUUCUUGUGGACAUUCAAAGUCCUCCAGAGUUUACCCUUGGACCCACCUUCCUAAUCUGAUUCCCUUUUCCUCAUUUCUUAAAUCCUUUGUUCCAACCAAACUGAUUUCUUUGGUGCUCUAAUUCUUCCUUAUUUUUGGUUCUCCUGCUUUUGUUUGAGCCUCUCACCUGAUCAGGUGUGCCCGCUCUCUUGCUUUCUGCCUAUACAAAUCCCAUGCAUCCUUCCAUGUUUACCUCCAUCCCCACUCUGCUGAGCGUGUUAUUGCUAACCCUGUGACCAGGCUGCACGCCAUAAUUCUGUUCCACAGAACUCCAGUCACAACUAUCACUCCUUCAGUUCUUUGACUAUAUCCAUGUACUACUGGGUGGCAUCUCUCCCACAUUGCCCUGAACUCUUUUCCUGAUAUUUAACUUAAUUUUUCUCCCCAAGUAAAUUGUAAAUUCCUGGAAGUGGGACGGCUAGUAUUUCAGGAGCAGUCACCAAAGCUCUGCCAUGUUUCUCACCUGUGUUCUCUUCUGAUACUGUUCAACAGCUUUGAAAUAGGUAAGGUGCUUACCAUUUCGCUGGUCAGGAUGCUAAUUCUUAGAAAGGUCAAGUAACUUACAGCUGCUGUUACCACAGAUUCAAGGCGAAGUCUGCCUAAGUCCAAAGCUGCUUCUGCUGCCACAUGCUACCUCCCUGCCAGCACCUCCCACCCCUGUAUGCAGGGUCAAGCAAGAGUGAUAAUAGAGUGACAUCCUUCAGAGACCUCAUUCAUGACCAAGAUGAAGAUGAGGAGGAAGAGGAAGGCCAGAGGAGCAGGUUUUAUGCUGGGGGCUCAGAGAGAAGUGGACAGCAGAUUGUUGGCCCUCCCAGGAAGAAAAGUCCCAACGAGCUGGUGGAUGAUCUCUUUAAAGGUGCCAAAGAGCAUGGAGCUGUAGCUGUGGAGCGAGUGACCAAGAGCCCUGGAGAGACCAGUAAACCGAGACCAUUUGCAGGAGGUGGCUACCGCCUUGGGGCAGCACCAGAGGAAGAGUCUGCCUAUGUGGCAGGAGAAAAGAGGCAGCAUUCCAGCCAAGAUGUUCAUGUAGUAUUGAAACUCUGGAAGAGUGGAUUCAGCCUGGAUAAUGGAGAACUCAGAAGCUACCAAGACCCAUCCAAUGCCCAGUUUCUGGAGUCUAUCCGCAGAGGGGAGGUGCCAGCAGAGCUUCGGAGGCUAGCUCACGGUGGACAGGUGAACUUGGAUAUGGAGGACCAUCGGGACGAGGACUUUGUGAAGCCCAAAGGAGCCUUCAAAGCCUUCACUGGCGAGGGUCAGAAACUGGGCAGCACUGCCCCCCAGGUGUUGAGUACCAGCUCUCCAGCCCAACAGGCAGAAAAUGAAGCCAAAGCCAGCUCUUCCAUCUUAAUCGACGAAUCAGAGCCUACCACAAACAUCCAAAUUCGGCUUGCAGACGGCGGGAGGCUGGUGCAGAAAUUUAACCACAGCCACAGGAUCAGCGACAUCCGACUCUUCAUCGUGGAUGCCCGGCCAGCCAUGGCUGCCACCAGCUUUAUCCUCAUGACUACUUUCCCGAACAAAGAGCUGGCUGAUGAGAGCCAGACCCUGAAGGAAGCCAACCUGCUCAAUGCUGUCAUCGUGCAGCGGUUAACAUAACCGCCCAGCCAGCUGCCUGGCCUCCCUCCUGUGUUUCCCAUGGCCAGUGGCCAUGCCCCAUGGGGAUCGCCCCUCCUGCCCCCUUGUGCACACCCAGCAGUCCAGUGCAACGUCUCCUCCAUAGCUCUGGGUUCUUAGAUCUUGGUUGGACGUUUGUUUUCUCCUUAGUUGCAUUUCCUGGGUUUUUGUGAUGAUCAAUGGACUUUAAUGAAAAAAAAAAUAAAAACAACCAAAAAAAUUGAAGGAAUAUCACCAGCAUGUUGUACGGAAACUCUCCCACUGAAGCAGGCUUUAAUUGCUUUAAAAUUAUAUUUAUCUUGGGGCCUGUGGGAGGAAACUUCCUUCCAUCUUCUCUGCAUAAAAACUUGUGGCACACAAUGCUUAUUCACUAGUGUGUCCCACCCGCCAGCCCCACAGAUGACUGGAGGAAGGAGGGGAAAUGUGUAGAAAGAGGCUUCGCCACCACUUGUUCCCACGAGAAUAUGUCACUUGCCCAGAUAAAACUGGGCGGCAGCCAGAGUUCCCUGAAGUGGGAAGUCAGAGCUCCAUGCACACAGUGUCUUCAGAAGGUGAAAAUAAAUAUUUCCCUGUGCUCCUUUUACUCAACCCCUGGGGUAUCUAAUCUUGCCAGGUCUUGGCCAGUUGAGAUUCUGUUCCACCUGCCUGCCUGGCCCUUUCCUCCAUUACCAUCCAGACUGCUCGCCUCCUGGGGAUUCUCAGGGGCUCCAUUAUGGCUUGAUUUACUCCACGUGCAGAAGUCUUGAGUGGACCUAGGAGGUAGGUGGGAUAUUUUUUUUCACUAGGAUACAGCUCAUGCCAACCCAUCCUAAGUGAGUUCAGAAUCAGGGUAUCUUGCCCUAUAAGAUAAACAGUCAAAAUGCCACCGAGCUGUUCACUAGUGAUGUGUGGCAAAUCAAAUCAACUGUUGAAGAAGGGGUGAGUUUUCUGUGCUACAAGCACCUGUCACUGUUGGUACUUGCAGGAGGCUUCUGCUGGGUAUGUUUUGGAAGUGAGUGUCACUACUUGGCUUUGCUUAGCAGGUUCUGCUUCACACUUGUUCUUUGACCUGCUGACUUGUGACUUGCAGAAACAUAGGCAGUAGUCCUAGCCUGGUAAAGACCCUCCACCACCCCUAUAAGUUUGAUUGCUAUGCAGGUUUGGGAGAGGAGGCCUAUUGGGCUCUUGGAUGGAACCCUUUCCCGUAUUAAACAAACCAGAGACAGAAUCAGUGCUGACUCAGGAUCUCCUGGUUUGGAAUCGUAAUGUGCCUCAAUCCUCUUUCCAAGCAGGCCUCACCAGUCUCUUUCUCUUUCCUGCUUCACCCCUGCAAUGAGCCAAGAACCAACACUACAUCCACCUAGAACUGCAGAAGGGCUUGUGGUUUCAACCAAGACCCAUCCUGAGCAAGGGACUUGGCUUGGUGCUUUUGAUCCCAAAGUUCCCACACCGGCAGUGGCCUGCUGGGGCAAUGGCAUCUGUCACGGUGUUUUCUCCAGCAGGUGGAGAUUAUGGAACCUACAUAUGGGUCUGGAAAAACUGUACACUGUUGUCACCUUGACCAUUAAAAACCAGAAUGAGGACAA